AGAAAACCCAAGUGCAGUAGAAGCCAUUGUUCAUAAUGGUAGGGAUACAGGGUCCUUCGUAACAGAUUAUCAGUGUGGCCUAUGCUGGAAAGUCUGGUGACCUCUGAUUUUUUUUGCUUCCAGGUCUUUGGCCUUGGCACUCUUUGUCAUAUUAGAGUUCCUGGGUCUAGGCCUGGGCAGGAUUCAUAGGUGCAGCUGCUUCUGCUGGAGGUAGACUGCAUCCAACAAAGUAAGGGUGCUGGGUGAGUUCUGGGAGUAUAGAUUCUGACUGGGGUCACUGCUGGGCUGGCCGCCAGUCUUUCAUCUGACCCAGGGUUAAACUGUGGCUUGGGACUGACUCAGGUCCUCUCUUGGGGUCGGUCUGCACAUAAAAGGACUCCUAUCCUUGGCAGUUCUGAAACAACACCACCACAAUGGAAAAAGCAUUGAAAAUUGACACACCUCAGCAGGGGAGCAUUCAGGAUAUCAAUCAUCGGGUGUGGGUUCUUCAGGACCAGACGCUCAUAGCAGUCCCGAGGAAGGACCGUAUGUCUCCAGUCACUAUUGCCUUAAUCUCAUGCCGACAUGUGGAGACCCUUGAGAAAGACAGAGGGAACCCCAUCUACCUGGGCCUGAAUGGACUCAAUCUCUGCCUGAUGUGUGCUAAAGUCGGGGACCAGCCCACACUGCAGCUGAAGGAAAAGGAUAUAAUGGAUUUGUACAACCAACCCGAGCCUGUGAAGUCCUUUCUCUUCUACCACAGCCAGAGUGGCAGGAACUCCACCUUCGAGUCUGUGGCUUUCCCUGGCUGGUUCAUCGCUGUCAGCUCUGAAGGAGGCUGUCCUCUCAUCCUUACCCAAGAACUGGGGAAAGCCAACACUACUGACUUUGGGUUAACUAUGCUGUUUUAAGCUUUGGAGGAAGAUGUGGAAAUGCUGUUUUCCUGAGCACACUGAUGAAUUCCAGGGCCCUGCAGGCAUUGCCCCAACCUCCUCAUCCCAUCCUGAUGUCUUCUUCCAUUCAGCAUUUGAGUGACCACAUUGAUGUUAGAGAUUACAUUUUUUCCUGGUGACAGCAUAGCACUCCCCGAGCUUUUCAUUUCUCAUGGUUCCUACAAAAAAGUAGAACUGUUUCUUCUCUGCCUUUCCCUGUGCUGGUAAUUCCUCUAGACCUGUGAGAUGACCAAAACACUUAGGAGAGUGAAAGGGGUCUAUGAAUGCACGAGGUUAAUGGACCUAAACUGAGAUGUAUGGACCAGCUGUUGGACCAACUGGGAUAUUGGAUCUCCUAAACUCAGGGCUGGGGAGAAAUCUGGCCAUCUUUGACGUUGCCUGGAUGUUUUCUGGAAGAAGCAAUUCAACUUCUUUAGAAAUUUAUGUCUACUUGUUUUUAUUCUCCUUUAUUUUCUUAUAAAUGCAUAAAACAUUGCAUUUUCUCUUAGUAUUCCUUGAGAUACAUCCUAUAAUUACUUGUAUUAUGGCUUAAAAUGAGAUAUACUUGCCUAAUAAAUUUUUAAAUGUACAAUAUUGUUAAUAAAGUAUACUGUAGGUAUACUCUUGUACAGAUCUCUAGAACUUACUUCUCUUGCUUAAAUGAAUAUUAUAUGCAUUGAAGAGCAUCCCUUCAUUUCUCCUUCCCCCAGUCCCUGGAAACCACCAUUCUACUCUCUGUUUCUAUGAAUUUGACUAUUUCAGAUAUCGUAUCUGUAAGUGGAAUCAUGCAGUAUUUGUCGUUUUGUGACUGGCUCAUUUCACAUAGCAUGAUAUACUCCAGGUUCUUCCAUGUUGUCCCAAAUGGCUGGAUUUUCUUCUUUUUAAAGGCUGAA